ACAUAGCUCCCGCCAAGUCCUCGGUGCCCCUUGCCAUUUUCCAGCCGCGCUCCCACGAGGGUCACGGCGGCGGGGAGAGGUGGAGCCGCGAGAGCUCGGCCGGGGGCCCCGCCUGGUGGCCGCGGCCAUGACAGCGGCUCGGGACUGGCUCCUUUUCCGCGCCCCUCCCGCCGGAGGUGAGGGGAAGAUGUCCAUGUCAGGGUUCAAGGCCAAACCGAAGUUACUGGCCUCUAUCUUCCAGGAGAACCAGGAGCCACAGCCGCGGCUCACGCCCCACCGCAACAUUAAGAUUACAAGUGGACACCUGAGUCAGCAGGACCUGGAAUCCCAGAUGAGAGAGCUUAUCUACACGACUCAGAUCUUGUUGUCACCCCCAUUAUUGACAAUCCAAAGGUGCAGAAAGCACUCUGACAAAUAAUGAAACAACCACCAUCGGUUAAAUUUGAUGCAAAAAUAUUGCAUCUACCAGCAUUUUCAGUUCCAAUUGCUAAUCCAGCAUUUGUGGAUAGCUGCAAACUGCGAUAUUGCUGAUGAGCGCUUUGACGCCACAUUCCACACUAACGUGUUGGUGAAUUCUUCUGGGCAUUGCCAGUACCUGCCUCCAGGCAUAUUCAAGAGUUCCUGCUACAUCGAUGUACGCUGGUUUCCCUUUGAUGUGCAGCACUGCAAACUGAAGUUUGGGUCCUGGUCUUACGGAGGCUGGUCCUUGGAUCUGCAGAUGCAGGAGGCAGAUAUCAGUGGCUAUAUCCCCAAUGGAGAAUGGGACCUAGUGGGAAUCCCCGGCAAGAGGAGUGAAAGGUUCUAUGAGUGCUGCAAAGAGCCCUACCCCGAUGUCACCUUCACAGUGACCAUGCGCCGCAGGACACUCUACUAUGGCCUCAACCUGCUGAUCCCCUGUGUGCUCAUCUCCGCCCUCGCCCUGCUGGUGUUCCUGCUUCCUGCAGAUUCCGGGGAGAAGAUUUCCCUGGGGAUAACAGUCUUACUCUCUCUUACCGUCUUCAUGCUGCUCGUGGCUGAGAUCAUGCCCGCAACAUCCGAUUCGGUACCAUUGAUAGCCCAGUACUUCGCCAGCACCAUGAUCAUCGUGGGCCUCUCGGUGGUGGUGACGGUGAUCGUGCUGCAGUACCACCACCACGACCCCGACGGGGGCAAGAUGCCCAAGUGGACCAGAGUCAUCCUUCUGAACUGGUGCGCGUGGUUCCUGCGAAUGAAGAGGCCCGGGGAGGACAAGGUGCGCCCGGCCUGCCAGCACAAGCAGCGGCGCUGCAGCCUGGCCAGUGUGGAGAUGAGCGCCGUGGCGCCGCCGCCCGCCAGCAACGGGAACCUGCUGUACAUCGGCUUCCGCGGCCUGGACGGCGUGCACUGUGUCCCGACCCCCGACUCUGGGGUAGUGUGUGGCCGCAUGGCCUGCUCCCCCACGCACGAUGAGCACCUCCUGCACGGUGGGCAACCCCCCGAGGGGGACCCGGACUUGGCCAAGAUCCUGGAGGAGGUCCGCUACAUUGCCAACCGCUUCCGCUGCCAGGACGAAAGCGAGGCGGUCUGCAGCGAGUGGAAGUUCGCCGCCUGUGUGGUGGACCGCCUGUGCCUCAUGGCCUUCUCGGUCUUCACCAUCAUCUGCACCAUCGGCAUCCUGAUGUUGGCUCCCAACUUCGUGGAGGCCGUGUCCAAAGACUUUGCGUAACCACGCCUGGUUCUGUACAUGUGGAAAACUCACAGAUGGGCAAGGCCUUUGGCUUGGCGAGAUUUGGGGGUGCUAAUCCAGGACAGCAUUACACGCCACAACUCCAGUGUUCCCUUCUGGCUGUCAGUCGUGUUGCUUACGGUUUCUUUGUUACUUUAGGUAGUAGAAUCUCAGCACUUUGUUUCAUAUUCUCAGAUGGGCUGAUAGAUAUCCUUGGCACAUCCGUACCAUCGGUCAGCAGGGCCACUGAGUAGUCAUUUUGCCCAUUAGCCCACUGCCUGGAAAGCCCUUCGGAGAGCUCCCCAUGGCUCCUCACCACCGAGACAGUUGGUUUUGCAUGUCUGCAUGAAGGUCUACCUGAAAAUUCAACAUUUGCUUUUUGCUUGUGUACAAACCCAGAUUGAAGCUAAAAUAAACCAGACUCACUAAAUCCUUUCCAAUAAUUGACUGGUGGAAGGAAAACAAAAAACAAAAACUAAAAACCUCUUAGCUUUUCUGCAAUUCAACUUUUUAUUUUUAUUUUUAUUUCUAUCAAAGACGGUAGAGAGAAACAGCUUGAUGCUGUUUCUACAUUAAAAAAAAAAAAAAAAAAAGACAGACUGUUGGUCUUACUAAGGAUGUUUUUACCAGCCUGCCUGACUUCUGCAAACCUACCCUGUCAAGGAGAUCAAAGGGACGCAGGUUUCUGUUUAUUCUGAACAAGGGCCAGGCCCCGCGGAGUGUCUUUGGUGGAUCCCAGAUAACUCCUAGGUGCUGCUCUCAGACACUGAGGAGUUGAGCAAAUCUGUUCUAUUCUGCAGAACCCAUAGGACAAAUAAGAGUUCUACUAGAAUUAACAGCCCAAAAGAAUAGCUACAGCUAAGUGAAGCCACUUACGUGGGCUUUAAAAAAAUAAUGUGUUAGCUGAUUCACAUGCACUGGAGUUAAUUAGUCUUAGAAAUGUGUGCAUCCAUACAAAUGCACAACAUAAAGUGAACAUAUUCCUAGGCCCUUUCUGCCUGUGUCAGGGCCAGGAAGUAGAGGCUGGGAACUCUUCUGGUCCCCAGUAUGGCAGGCGCCAGGGAGGGGAUGGUGUGGCCCAUCCCUUCUCUGGAUACCUGGCCAGUGGCAGGCAGCAGGGAGGAGCUGGCCGACCCUCAGUGACUGACAAGCCAGCAAUUCUGAGUUCUGGCCUUUGGGAGUCUGCCUGCUCCAAGCCAGUCCACCCCAGCUGCAGCCCCAAAAGCUGGCUCAAAGUCCUUGGGUGGAUUCACUGGAGAUGGGCAACUUAAAACAAGAGAAACUUUAAUUUUUAAACCUAAGUGAUGAUACAGCUCUUCCCUUAGAUUAUCGCCCAGGCUGGAGUGCAGUGGCAUGAUCUCAGCUCACUGCAAGCUCCACCUCCCGGGUUCAUGCCAUUCUCCUGCCUCAGCCUCCCCCCGAGUAACUGGGAAUACAGGCGCCCGCCACCAUGCCUGGCUAAUUUUUUGUAUUUUUAGUAGAGAUAGGGUUUCAUCAUGUUAGCCAGGAUGGUCUCAUUCUUAUUCUUUAAUGAGAUCAGAGGGUAAUUCACCAAGAAAGACCUCUCCUGUUCCAUUGUGUCAUCCAACAACUGCUCAGAGCUCAAAAUUAUAGAAGGCUUCUGAGCCCCUAGAGAUUUUUAAUUUGCUUCUAAUCCCUGAGGUGGGAACAUCAUGAGGGAAGAUUUGAUUUUCAGAGUUAAAUAAAUUGUAUGUGCUUUUCCAGCCA